CUCUCUCCAUCGUCUCCUGGUGCCCUGGGCCCCUCCGCAUCCGAACCUGGGGGGAGGAUGAGGUUGGUGGCCUUUGACCGUACUCGCCUCCCGCCGGGCCAGCAUCUAACUAAGCCCGCCUGGCCGCCCUUCUCGGGCGCGCAGUUGUCUCGAGUGUGGGUACCCACCUCCACCCCCACCCUCACCCGGGUGAACUAGCGGGGGUUCUAGAGAGUGCCGGCUCCCAGUGAGCCCUCUCCAACAGCUGCGGGCCACGAGAUCCUGAGAACCUGGGCCCAGCGCUCAGCCCAGGCCCGCCCCUUCCCGGGCAGCCCCGUCGCUCCGCGUCCUAGGGGGCGGGCGGGAAGGAUGGGACCCCCGCCUAGGAGGCGCGCAGGCGCCGCCGAGCGCGGGAGAGAAAGAGUUAAACUAGGUGCCGGCGCCGGGCGCGGCGGGAGUGGGGGAGGGGAGCGAAGAGAAAGUGAGAGCGGGGGCGGAGCGGGGACGGGAGCGAAAGAACAUCCUGUGCCCGUCGCCGGAUGCGCGCGGGGGGAGGAGGUAGUCCGGGGAGGGAGAGCAAGACCGGGGGAGGCCCGGGACGGGGAAAGGCGCGGCCUCCUUCCCCCCGCCGCAACCUCCUCCUCUGGGGGCGCUGGCCCCCUCUGCUCCCCGCGCCUUAGGCUGAGCUACCCGGAGGCCCCAGGAUCUGGUUCCUGGGCAGGAGUAAGCGCUAGCUGGGGAGAUGAUCUCGGAGAGUGUGGGAUCCACGUUAAGGCAGGGGCGGCCCCCAGCCUUUCAUCUCUUGGCUUUCUGCAAGGGAAGCUCGCACGUGUUGAGCGUCCCCUGUGCACCGAAAGUACACACAUUAUCUCAGUCCUGACAGCGGCACUUCCAGGCAGUAGACAGGAAUUCAUAGACUCGCAUUCUAGAGGAGGAAACAGACUCAGAUUAUGGAAUUUGUCCAAACCCCACACUGUUGGGAUGUGAAUGCAAGCCUGUCGGACUGCAAAGGGCUUUUCACUGGAGUUUAGGGCAGAACCAGAAGAAAUGGGCCUUAGGUGUGGCAGGAGGGAGUUAGGUUGCAGCCAAGAAAGAACACUUUUUGGAGGUCUUUAAAGAACAGGUGAGCCUUACCUGUGCUUAGGAAGUGAGGGUUGCAGAAUCGGCUCCAUGGGAUGGAGGGGCCAGUAACUCUGGGUCCCACCCUGGAGAAGGGCAGAGCAAGGACCUUGUCUUGAGGGAUUUAUUCUCAGAUCCACCAAAGUAGCCUGGGAACCUAAAUGACAGUUCCCAUCAGGCAGCCGUUUUCUGCUCGGAGUUCAGUGGAGAUGCGAUGGGGUUGCAUGGCAGUGGGGAGGCUUCCAUGGGCUUCUACUCACCCCUCACCACAGGGAGUUCAUGUAGUCACCCACCUUGGGGCUAAAUAGAGUGCCAGGAAUGAUGACCCUUGAGGAGGGCUGAGGACAGGAAUAGAAUGGCCACCCAGGAGUGUUGCUUGUUCCCUGCCUGCUGCCUAGGGUGUACUGGGCCAAGGCUCUGAGUGGGCAGGCCUGGCUGGCCGCAGCAUCAUUGGAGAUGCUGUUUCCCUACCUCCUUCCAUCCUGGGUGCAGCCCAGGACCCAGAGCCUUCUGUCCCAGUUCUCCCAAAAAGGGAUCAGGGCCAGGUAGGUGAACACCUGUUCUGGUGCAGCAUGCUCAGCACUGGCUGUGGGCGUGGCCCUAGUUUGGAGCUGGCCACUUGCCUGUUCUGCAACAGAGAGUGGGGACAGAAGUUGCGGGGAGACCCUGGUGGGGAAGAGGGAAGGGUCUGGUCUCACCUGCCCCAUCCUAGUGGUGGGGAUCAAGACCUCCACAGGUGGGCUCACAUCCUCUGGGGUGGUGGCAUCUUCUGACUCCAGAGGACCUCACAAGCCGCCUCAUAUCCCUGGGGAGGCUGAGAGGUGAUACUUCCAAAUUUAGCUGAAAGGCACAGACUUACCCACAUUUUAAUCCUGGAGUUUUAGAAUGGUAAAUCCGAAUCCCUUUAGGUUACAAAUGCAGAAACAGACUAAGGCAAAGGCGAUCCCUUUCUCCUCCAAGGUCACUCUGGUUAGAAGGGUCUGGAGCCCCAGUUACUAGAUGCUGUCAUUGUUCUGCCGCCAAGUCCUUAAAGAAUGGCAGAACAUGACUUAAACCACCUGCUAAGUACAAGAUUCUAUGCUGGAGAUGCAAAGGUAGCUGUCCUCAAGAGCACUUUGUCAAACAGGUAAACUUCAGGGCAACAUGCAGAUGCUGGAAAAGGGUGGAUUUGCCUCAAGAGUCUGUGCAUGCUUUCUAAGAUACUCCCCUCCUUUUCAUCCUCUGAUGCGGGGAGGGAACCCUACCUGAAGAAACACCCCAAGGCCCAGGGGUAGAUCUAGGGUGGAGAGAUCACAUAUGGGAGGGCCCGGAAAGAAAAGGAACAGGGUUGUCAAUGGGCAUACCCCAAACACCUCACCCAGAAAUGCCCUAAGGCCCCAGCCCGGAAAUGGACCUCUGCUGCCCUCUAAUGGUGGAAAGGCAGCCUCUGGAGCUACCUGCUGGGGUCCCCCCUUAAAGAAGAGGAGAUGUGAAGGACACUUCUGCCCUCUCCCCUUUUAUUCCCCUUCUGUCUUAUGCUUCAUCUCCUGUGGUCUCUAAAGCAGAACCUUCUCUUUUUUUUUUUGAAAUGGAGUCUUGCUCUGUCGCUUAGGUUGGAGUACAGUGGCGUGUCAGCUCACUGCAACCUCAACCUCCCAGGCUUAAGCGAUUCUCCUGCCUCAGUCCCCUGAGUAGCUGGGAUUACAUGUGUGCGCCACAAUGCCUGGCUAAUUUUUUUGUAUUUUUAAUAGAGACAAGGUUUCACCAUAUUGGCCAGGCUGGUCUCGAACUGCUGACCUCAAGUGAUCUGCCUGCCUUGGCCUCCCAAAGUGCUGGGAUUACAAGUGUGGGCCAUGGUGCCUGGCCCCAUCUGUUCUCGAGCACUCCUGGCUGCCCCAUUUCCUGACCACUGCCCUCCAUCCCAUUAUCUCCCCAGUUUCCUUUGUUGCCUAGGUUCCAAUUCUGGUACCCUGGUUCCUGACCCUGCCAGAGUUCUGGUUCCGGAAGGCCCCCCACAGGUGCCUUGGGCCUAGCUCUCACCUGGGCCCAGGGCAACACUGAAGACAUGGGCAAGAGCAUCCCCCAAUACCUGGGGCAACUGGACAUCCGCAAAAGCGUAGUCAGCCUGGCCACAGGCGCCGGGGCGAUCUACCUGCUCUACAAGGCCAUCAAGGCUGGCAUAAAAUGCAAACCACCCCUCUGUAGCAACUCACCCAUCUGCAUCGCCCGCCUGGCAGUCGAGCGAGAGCGGCACGGGCGGGACUCAGGUGAGCUCCGGAGGCUCCUCAACUCUUUGGAGUGCAAACAGGAUGAGUAUGCCAAGAGCAUGAUCCUGCACAGUAUCACUCGCUGUGUGUACUUGCUGGAGGCUGAGGCCUCUGCUUGUACUACGGAUGACAUCGUGUUGCUGGGCUACAUGCUGGAUGACAAGGACAACAGUGUCAAAACCCAAGCUCUGAAUACACUUAAAGCUUUCUCUGGCAUCAGAAAAUUCAGGCUCAAAAUCCAGGAACACUCCAUCAAAGUACUCGAACUGAUCUCCACCAUCUGGGACACGGAACUGCACAUUGCGGGCCUCAGACUCCUCAACAACCUUCCACUGCCCGACUAUGUGCAUCCACAGCUGCGACGGGUGAUGCCUGCCUUGAUGGAGAUCCUGCAGUCAGACUACAUCCUGGCACAGGUGCAAGCCGUACGACUGCUGAGCUACCUGGCACAGAAGAAUGACCUUCUCUAUGACAUUCUCAACUGCCAGGUUCACUCCAACUUCCUAAACCUGUUCCAGCCCACACAGUCAGGGAGUCUCCUGUAUGAGGUACUGGUGUUUGCUGAGCGGCUGAGUGAGGGCCGGAACGCACCCCACUACCACGUGGUGAAAUGGCAUUACAACGAACAGUCCCUGCAUGAAUCCCUCUUUGGGGAAGAGUCCCGACUGGCAGACCGACUACUUGCCCUGGUCAUCCACCCUGAGGAAGAUGUUCAGAUCCAGGCCUGCAAGGUCAUUGUCAGCCUGCAGUAUCCCCAGGACUUGAGAGCCCGGCCCUCCUCCUGCCAGCCCAGUCGUUCCUACUUUAAAAACACGGAAUAAAAUUAAGGAGAGCCAAUAAAUGAGUAUAGGAGAGAAACUUGAAGUUUCUUGAAGCUCGAAUGUCUGUUGGUGGCCUUCCAGGGCUGGGUGGAGAUUUCAUUCAGCAUAACCUCUGCUCCAGAGUGUGGUACAGCAUGGGCUUAUCUCUCAAAACACAUCCCCACUUCUAUGUUUGGGGGACUAGCUCCCCUCUUCUCUUGCUGCUUUUC